CAUCUUUUACUGUGAGGGCGAGCUGCACGGGAAGCCGGUCCGAGGGGUGAAGCUCGUGGGUGGGUCCCGCACCCUCACCCUGCAACCCAUGCCUCCACCUGCCCUCCCUCCUCCCUCGGCCUCCUGCACCCUCUUCCCCAUGGGAGAAGCCACUGGGACCCAGGAACCCACUGCAGUUUUCUUAGGAUGAGUUUUCCUGAUAAAGGCCUCAAUUCCCACCCCUGGAGUUCAGGAUUUGGGAUGCCCCGGCCUCGGUAUCUGCAGCAGAGGCAGGAAGGAGCCACGGCUGCAGGCACAGGGGUUCAAAGGUCACACAUGUCCCAGAGUGGGCCAGGCCCUCCCCCGGAGCAGCUCCCUGCAGUGUCAUCCUUGAGCGCGUUCCUGUGGGGUGUCCAGCAGGAGAGAGGAACAGGGAUGUGAGCAGAAGUCUGCAUGGAAAGAACGUUCCAGCUCCCGGGGUUGAAUUCCGGACGCGGUGCCUCCCACAGAUGGUGACUCAUCAGUGCUGUCCCUGUCAGAGGACGAGGCCCAUGAAGGCUCCUGAGUUCUCCCUGGAGCCAGGGGUGUGCGAAUGACAGAGGAUUGGGAUCCUGGUGCCCCCAAGGGGAGAGGCGCUUCCUCCAGGGUGGGCCUGUCGUGCCGUCCAUCCUCACUCCGGGAGAUGCUCAGGGAUGGAUGGAGAGCCCUUCCCGUUCUCCCGGUUCUGCUGCCACAGGAGCCUUCUCAGCCGUGCACGGCACCCUGGUCCCACUUUGCCAGCCUGAGGGCCUCUGGGUUCAAUUCCCCCCACGGUGGGCGAGGUCCCCUUCCCCAGCCCAGCUCAGGCCUCCAGACUGGGAUGGGGUGCCGUCGGCCCAGUGCUGCCUCGAGCACCCACAUCUCGUCCUGGCACCCACAGGCAGAGACCCCAAGAACAACCUGGAAGCCUUGGAGGACUUUGAGAAAGCCGCAGGAGCCCGCGGACUCAGCACGGAGAGCAUCCUCAUCCCCAGGCAGAGCGAAACCUGCUCUCCAGGGAGCGAUUAGGGGCAGGGGACACCUUGGCUCCUCAGCAGCCCAAGGACGGCACCAUCCAGCACCUCCGUCAUUCACAGGGACAUGGAAAAAGCUCCCCACCCCUGCAGAACGCGGCUGGCUGCACCCCUUCCUACCACCCCCCGCCUUCCCCCUGCCCUGCGCCCCCUCUCCUGGUUCUCCAUAAAGAGCUUCAGCAGUUCCCAGUGA